GGGCUCAUGAAUAAUGAAUCUGGAGCCCUGGUAAAUCUCCCCCUCCCACUGCCUCAGCCUCGUGCUGCUCGGGAGGAAGGCCCUCUAGGCUCCCCUGCCAGCCUGGUCCCCCCCUUCACCCCUGCCUCCCUGCCUCCCUGUUCCUCCUCACCGGGCCUGGCUCAGGCCCCCAUGUGCAAGGAUUCCGAAGGGAAGGGUGAAGGAUUUUGGUUGGGCAGCAGGCAGAGGAACUGGGGCCACAGGCCUAGAGGCUGAUCCCCACAGCCCGCUCUGCUCGGUUCCCGCUGAGCCCAGCCCUGGCCGGUUUUCCGCUUUGCCAGCUCCAUCUGCUCCCAGCUUGGCUUUUGGCAGGGUGGGGGUUUUGCCUCUGCCCGAGGCCUCAUGUCUCUGUCUUCUACUCCCCUGGCAGGCUGGGUGGGCCUGAGCUGGUGCCAUUCUCUUCGGAAGCACAGUGGGAGGUACCCUGUUCUGGGAAGGCCCUCACCACCUCCUGUCCCCCUGGCCCUGCCCUUUGAGGUUGAAGGCAUCCUGCCUACCCUCAGGAGGAAAGAGGAUGUGAUUUGUCUCAUGAUGGAGGCCAGUAUGUUGUCGGGGAAGUGUGACCCCAAGAUCUCAAUAGAUGCUGCUGGUUCUGCGGCUUGGAUCGAUGGAGCCACCUCCCCCCGCCCGUCCACGCUUCCUCUCCCUGCUGCUCAUUAGCGCCCCGAUUAAUCAGCCCCCCUUUCCUCCCGGGGACAAGGGCUUCCUCCCCCGUGAGGGCACAUGCUGUCGGAUGGGGCCCCAGAGCACAAGCACUGAUUCUUGCCACCCCCACCCUGGGGGCAUGGAUGCAUCCCCUCCUGGCCAGUCAACUGAGGCUCCCACCCCCACCUAUGAUGAUGGCCCACAUGCCUGUUCCCCUCCACGAGAACACAGCAGACCCCUUAGGGCUCUCCUGCCCCACUCUGCCAGGCACCCCUCAAACCCCUUUCUUUAGGAGAGCAUUCGCUCCCAUUGACGCCCAGCACAUCUUCCUGCUCCCUUCCACGCCCCCACUGGGGCUCUUCCUCUCCCUCCAUUGCAUGCCCUGUCCCCCUACAUAUAGAGCACCCCGGAAGCACACCUCCCCUUUGCUCCCUGGCUUGCUUACCCAACAGCCCUCCCCCGAAGCCUGGUUGUGGCAAGGGAUUUGGGGAACAUUUGGGGAAGCAAAGUGGCCACAGAUAUGCAAGCUGGCCAGGGUGCUGUCUGUCCCAGACAUAUGAAUGACUGAGAUUGGGGUUGGGGGCAAAAUGAGGGUGAGGGCAGCCAGCCUCCCAGAGGGGGCAGGGGCAUGGUGGGUGUUGAAGUCUGGAGCAAAGCUCCAGGGAAGCUGAGAAUCUUGAAGUCACAGUUGUCCCCUGGUCUGUCUAGCCUGCCCUCCUCUGCCCCCCUCCCUCCGUCAUUCAAACAAGUGGCUCUCUCAAGGAGUUUCUGGAAGCUGCUGUGAGUCGGGUAGUGGGAUCAGGUGGUGGCUGGGUGCUGGAGUCAGGAGUCUCAGAGGCCAGGAGGUGGGGGGAUAGAGUUGGCUGACCCUUCAUGGGGUGUGGGCCAGGAAAGUGGCAAAGAAUGAGCUGAGGACCCUGGGCACGGCACCCUUCCCUGGGUGGCCAGGAAGUGGGGAGAUCUGGGGACCCAGUGAGCGGCUAGGGUGCAGCAGGAGUUUGGGGGAUAGCCCCAGUCUUGGGAUCUCUGUCCUGGGCUGGGGACUGCCCCCUCCCCUGGCCUGGCUCCUGACGCCCGUGCUGCCGGUGAAACGCUGUUGACAUGUCCUGAAUUAUUAAGCGUGGGGAGGGCUCCGGAGCACAUGCUGAGCGGAGCGGCUGGGGCUGCGCGGCGUGGCGGAGCAGCGCUCGCUCCCUCGCUCACUCGCUCGCUCGCAGGGACACACGCAGGGGCUGACAGCUGUGCUGGUGCUGAUAAGGGAAGCCACAAGGAGACGAUCGAGGAGAGAGACAAGCGGCAGCAGAGGCAGCAGCGGCAGAGGCAGCACCAGGGCUGCGGAGCUGCUGGGAGUGGGAGUGACUCCCCCACCUCGGGCCCCCACCCUGUCCCUGUCCUCUUCCCGCUUGCCCUGAGUUUAGAAGAGCAGCCGCUGCCACCACUGCCACUCGGGAGGGCACCAGGGCUGCUGGCUAGGGAGGGACAGGGCAGGGAGGCUCUGGCCAGUCCCAGCAGCCGGGGACAGAUGCCGAUCGAGAUUGUGUGCAAAAUCAAAUUUGCUGAGGAGGAUGCGAAACCCAAGGAGAAGGAGGCAGGGGAUGAGCAGAGCCUCCUCGGGGCUGUUGCCCCUGGAGCAGCCCCCCGAGACCUGGCCACCUUUGCCAGCACCAGCACCCUGCAUGGACUGGGCCGGGCCUGUGGCCCAGGCCCCCACGGACUGCGCAGAACCCUGUGGGCACUGGCCCUACUCACCUCGCUGGCUGCCUUCCUGUACCAGGCGGCUGGCCUGGCCCGGGGCUACCUGACCCGGCCUCACCUGGUGGCAAUGGACCCCGCUGCCCCAGCCCCAGUGGCGGGCUUCCCGGCUGUCACCCUCUGCAAUAUCAACCGCUUCCGGCAUUCGGCACUCAGCGAUGCCGACAUCUUCCACCUGGCCAAUCUGACAGGGCUGCCCCCCAAAGACCGGGAUGGGCACCGUGCGGCUGGCCUGCGCUACCCAGAGCCUGACAUGGUAGACAUCCUCAACCGCACUGGCCACCAGCUCGCCGACAUGCUUAAGAGCUGCAACUUCAGUGGGCAUCACUGCUCCGCCAGCAACUUCUCUGUGGUCUAUACUCGCUAUGGGAAGUGUUACACCUUCAACGCGGACCCGCGGAGCUCGCUGCCCAGCCGGGCAGGGGGCAUGGGCAGUGGCCUGGAGAUCAUGCUGGACAUCCAGCAGGAGGAGUACCUGCCCAUCUGGAGGGAGACAAAUGAGACGUCGUUUGAGGCAGGUAUUCGGGUGCAGAUCCACAGCCAGGAGGAGCCGCCCUACAUCCACCAGCUGGGGUUCGGGGUGUCCCCAGGCUUCCAGACCUUUGUGUCCUGCCAGGAACAGCGGGUGAGCAUCUCCUGCUAGGCCCUGGAUUGGGCACAGGGCUCGCCUUUGGGCUCAGAGGGGAUGUGGAGCAAACCUGCCCUCUAGAAGCUCAGAGCCUGCCAGCUGUGUUGACUUUGCUGGGGCUGUGGGCACUGGAGGACUGGGUGGGAUUCCUGAGCAUGACCUCAUCAUGCCCCACCUCUGCAGCUGACCUACCUGCCCCAGCCCUGGGGCAACUGCCGCGCAGAGAGUGAGCUCAGGGAGCCUGAGCUUCAGGGCUACUCGGCCUACAGUGUGUCUGCCUGCCGGCUGCGCUGUGAAAAGGAGGCCGUGCUUCAGCGCUGCCACUGCCGGAUGGUGCACAUGCCAGGUGGGCACCCCACCCCCAGCCAGCCCUCCAUGCCACCCUGCUAGGCUCCAGAGCCUCCCGGGGCAAGGCACUGCUCAUGUGCACAGGCAGGUGCAUGUAUACAACAUGUGUAUGUGUCUGUACCCGUGUGAGUGUGAGUGUUUGGGAUUUUUAAACAUGGUUUCACAUAUGCAUGUGGGAAUGCCGGCAUGCAGAUGCCUGUGUGCAUGUUAAUAUGUAUUUGUGUACGUGCAUGCUCAUUUAUAUCCGUGGUUGCGUAUUUGUGGGGGUUGUGUGUGUGGUGUUCAAGCACAUUUAUGCAAAUGUGUGCAUAUGUGUGUGCAUGCAUGUAUGUGCUUACAUUUGGGCGUGUGGGGGACAGGGGAAGUGAUCGUAGAUUCCAGGAAUAAUCUUCUCUCCUUUCAGGCAAUGAGACCAUCUGCCCACCAAAUAUCUACAUCGAGUGUGCAGACCACACACUGGGUCCGUGCUGCCUACCCUUUCCUACCUCUCCAUCAGCCUCUUCAUGUCUCUGUCCACUCUUCUCCUCACUGUCUUGGAUCCUCCCCUCCCAAUCUCUUCCUGGAGGGUUCUUCCUGGGGGUUGAGCCUUAGCCCAUACUUCAGUGGGGUUGGGGAGAGGUCUGCGGACCUCUGCAGGUACAGACACUUGGGUAAGUGGAGGCAGCAGGGUGGGGGGUUGCAGAGAAGCCAGGACUGGGAGUGAAGGUCUGGGCUUCUCAUCUUGGUUCAGCCAAUGAGCUCACCCACUUUGAGAAAGUGAAAUGACUUCUCUCUUGGUCUCAGGAAAAAUGCAUUGCUGGCUAUCGGUGUGGGUAAGGCAAACCCCAUCUGUCCACAGAUCUUGCCUGAUCUGCAGUUCAUCCAUCUAUCCAUCCAUUCAUCGAUUCGCGCAUUCUCCAGACCUUUACAGCCUGUGCUGGGUACUGGAGGUGAGAGUGGGGGCGACAGCCCUGCCCUUGGAGAGCUUACACCCCGGCAGGGCUGUGGACAGCCAUUCCCACACAGCCCGUCAACUCCUGGAGAGGGGAGCCUCGGGUGUGCUGCAAGGCCCCAAGGAGGGGUGUGCAGCCCUAGCCUGGGAAGGUAGGGAGGAUUCCUAGAGGAAGGGACACAUUAGCUGAGGCUUGAUGGGUGUAUAAGAGUCAGGUGCAAAGGGGGACAUACACUGAAGACCUGUGGCCAGAAAGAGCAUGCUGUGUCCGGGGCACUGAAAGGUCUGUGUGGCUGCAGGGCAGAGAACAGGGGAGGGAGUAGAAAGAGUAGAGGAGGGAGGCCAGGCACGGUGGCUCACAAGUGUAGACCCAGCACUUUGGGAGGCCAGGGUCUGUGGAUCACUUGAGCCCAGUAGUUCAAGACCAGCCUGGGCAACAUGGUGAGACCCUGUCUCUGCAAAAAAUAAAAAAGUGAACUGGGUGUGGUGGUGCACAUCUAUAGUCCCACCUAUUCGGGAGGCUGAGGCAAGAGGAUAGGCUUGAGCCUGGGAGGUUGAGGCUGCGGUGAGCUGGGAUCACACCAUUGCACUCUAGUCUGAGCUACAGAGUUACCCUGUCUCA